GCUAGUCUCCAGCUCCAAAAUGGCGGCUGCCACUGUGGGGCUUCUGCCGGCCGGUAGUCCCUGGCGCUGCUGACCCAGCAUCGGCUUUUCUACGUCUUGAACCUGGAUUCGCCUAGGGGUUGGGAAGGGCUGUGGACGGCGUUGGGGGAGGCCUGACGAGGCAAGUGAGGGCGGGAGAAAGGAGCGAGCCUCGGGCUGGGGAAGGCGGCGUCAUUGGCCCUCCGGGAGCACGGGGCCCCGACUCCGACCCGGUCUCCCCCGAGGACUCGCCCCCGCCGCUUCGGCUGCGACUGUCCCGGUCGUUCCCGGCAGAAGUGGUCAGCGAGGGAAAGAGAAGUGACUUCUCCAUGGGUUUCAAGCUCCCAGCUGUUUUGCGGCAGCCCAUUAAUAAAGAACUCUUCAGAAUUCCUGGUGUUUCAUCAUAUAUACGACUAAGAUAUCAACUCUUCUAGCUUGCUGUUUCUGGACCAAAAAAAAUGACGUCUAUUAUCAAAUUAACUACCCUUUCUGGGGUCCAAGAAGAAUCUGCCCUUUGCUAUCUUCUCCAAGUUGAUGAGUUUAGAUUUUUAUUGGACUGUGGCUGGGAUGAGCACUUUUCUAUGGAUAUUAUUGAUUCCCUGAGGAAGCAUGUUCACCAGAUUGAUGCAGUGCUGUUGUCUCACCCUGAUCCUCUCCACCUUGGUGCCCUCCCGUAUGCUGUCGGAAAGUUGGGUCUGAACUGUGCUAUCUAUGCAACCAUUCCUGUUUAUAAAAUGGGACAGAUGUUCAUGUAUGAUCUUUAUCAGUCUCGACACAAUACAGAAGAUUUUACACUCUUUACAUUAGAUGAUGUGGAUGCAGCCUUUGAUAAAAUACAGCAGCUAAAAUUCUCUCAGAUUGUGAAUUUGAAAGGUAAAGGACAUGGCCUGUCUAUCACACCUCUGCCAGCUGGUCAUAUGAUAGGUGGAACAAUAUGGAAAAUAGUCAAAGAUGGAGAAGAAGAAAUUGUUUAUGCAGUUGACUUCAACCACAAGAGGGAGAUCCAUUUAAAUGGAUGUUCCCUGGAAAUGCUAAGCAGGCCUUCCCUACUUAUCACAGAUUCAUUCAAUGCUACAUAUGUACAGCCUAGAAGAAAACAGAGAGAUGAGCAGCUUCUGACAAAUGUCCUGGAAACACUUCGAGGUGAUGGAAAUGUGUUAAUAGCAGUGGACACAGCAGGCAGAGUUUUGGAACUUGCUCAACUUCUUGAUCAGAUUUGGAGGACUAAAGAUGCAGGAUUGGGUGUUUACUCAUUGGCACUCCUAAAUAAUGUCAGUUACAAUGUGGUGGAGUUUUCUAAGUCCCAGGUAGAAUGGAUGAGUGAUAAAUUGAUGAGAUGUUUUGAAGACAAAAGAAAUAAUCCGUUUCAGUUUCGCCAUCUCUCUUUAUGUCAUGGUCUUUCUGACUUGGCCCGUGUACCUAGCCCUAAAGUUGUACUUGCCAGCCAACCUGACCUGGAAUGCGGAUUUUCAAGGGAUCUCUUUAUUCAGUGGUGUCAGGACCCUAAAAACUCAAUCAUUCUAACCUACAGAACUACUCCUGGGACUUUAGCACGUUUCCUAAUUGAUAAUCCUUCUGAAAAAAUUACAGAAAUAGAGUUGAGGAAACGUGUGAAGCUUGAAGGGAAAGAACUUGAAGAAUACUUGGAAAAAGAGAAACUAAAGAAAGAAGCUGCCAAAAAGCUUGAGCAGUCAAAAGAGGCAGAUAUAGAUUCCAGUGAUGAGAGUGAUAUUGAGGAAGAUAUUGACCAGCCAUCAGCUCAUAAGACGAAGCAUGACUUGAUGAUGAAAGGUGAAGGCAGUCGUAAAGGAAGUUUUUUCAAACAGGCAAAAAAGUCCUAUCCUAUGUUUCCUGCCCCAGAAGAAAGAAUUAAAUGGGAUGAAUAUGGAGAGAUUAUCAAACCAGAGGAUUUCUUAGUGCCAGAGCUUCAAGCUACUGAAGAAGAAAAAAGCAAAUUAGAAUCUGGUUUGACAAAUGGAGAUGAACCUAUGGAUCAGGAUUUAUCUGAUGUUCCUACUAAAUGUAUUUCUACAACAGAGUCUAUUGAAAUAAAAGCCCGGGUUACCUACAUAGACUAUGAAGGACGCUCUGAUGGGGAUUCCAUUAAAAAAAUCAUUAAUCAGAUGAAACCACGACAGUUGAUCAUCGUCCAUGGCCCACCAGAGGCCAGUCAAGAUCUGGCAGAGUGCUGUCGCGCCUUUGGUGGGAAAGAUAUUAAAGUGUACAUGCCAAAGCUACAUGAAACAGUUGAUGCCACUAGUGAAACUCACAUCUACCAGGUGAGGUUAAAAGACUCACUUGUCAGCUCUCUUCAGUUUUGUAAGGCAAAAGAUGCUGAAUUAGCUUGGAUAGAUGGUGUCUUAGAUAUGAGAGUUUCCAAAGUGGACACAGGGGUUAUUUUAGAAGAAGGAGAACUAAAGGAUGAUGGAGAAGACUCAGAGAUGCAAGUGGAAGCUCCCUCAGAUUCUAGCGUUAUAGCACAACAAAAGGCCAUGAAAAGUCUGUUCGGAGAUGAUGAAAAAGAAACAGGUGAAGAAAGUGAGAUCAUUCCUACUUUGGAACCCUUGCCACCUCAUGAGGUUCCUGGACAUCAGUCAGUUUUUAUGAAUGAACCAAGGCUGUCAGACUUCAAGCAAGUUCUCUUACGGGAGGGGAUUCAAGCUGAAUUUGUAGGAGGUGUACUUGUUUGCAACAAUCAAGUAGCAGUCCGCAGAACGGAAACUGGACGCAUUGGAUUAGAAGGCUGCCUUUGUCAAGAUUUUUAUAGGAUAAGAGACCUUUUAUAUGAACAAUAUGCCAUUGUAUAAAGGACAUGAUGUCAAGAAGUAUCUGCUUGACCUUUCUAAGAAAAAGGGAUUCUUAUCUUACUCUGAGCUUUUGAUGUUUUGUUUUGUAACAUACAAAAAGAAUCUGCCAGAAAAACUUACAUGUAUCAGAUUUUUAAAAAUAUAAAUAGAGAACAUUUUGCAAAUGCUCAAAUGAGCAUUCUAUCUUUUGGCUUUCAGAGUGAUAGAGCUCCUAACAGGUGUACAGGCCCAAGAGUUGAAGGUGAUUGGUUUUCUUUACAGACUCCUUGUUCUCUAGAAGGGCUUUUUACUUGAAUAAAACAAUGCAACUUAGCAAACCAAUUUAUGGCCUUAGAGAAACAUUUUUGCAUGAGUUCUUACAAACUGUUUGUUAUAUUUUCUGGAAUGAUAAGUGAGAAUUAUUUAGAAAAGACAUGCUCCAAAAAAAAAACAAAACUGAUAAAACAGUUUUUCGAAACUUACUUUUAAAAGCAUACGUGCUAUGACUCUCUCCAGUUUGAAUAUGCAAUUGUUUUCACAGGCAGGAUGUCUGUUUUCUGCCUGUAUUUCCCAGUGAUUUACUCUAGGGUAAGGUAGUACACAUUUGGUUCAGAAAUUAAUUUUUAUUUCUCCUAUAUCUUGUUUUAUCAAGAUUUUGUUGUGGCAUUUCAAUGUAAAUUAUAACACCAUCAUUUGAGUAUACAUAAUUCAAAAGAACUACUUGAUGCAGUAUAGUCUUAAGGGUUCUGCAUACAUUUUAGAAACAUCUUAGCCGUAAGUUAGGUCCUGUGUUAAACUGUUUAGUGCUCUGUUUUUAAGAAAACAAAUGUUGAACCUCACACUUUUAUGUGGUGACAGUGUAAUUUAAUUAAAAGGUGUAAAUGUUUUCAUCUCUUAGGCUUGCUGUCUCCUAAGGUCACCCAAGCAGUGGUUGGAUUUUAUACACAUUACUACUAAAAUAAUACUGAAGUUGGAUAAGGUUAUCCUUUCUGUAUUUGCGUCUUUCUUGUGACUAACCACCCUGAUAUAGUAUUAACCACUGUGUUCAAGAGUAAAAACAAUAUAUGCAAUUUUCAUUGAACUUAAAGAGUGAAAACCAUGUAAACUAUUGAAACUAUUGUAAUCCAUUAAUGCUUUUUUAGAAUGGCAGACCUUGAUGUUUAUUUCUCAAAUGGUUAAGCCCUCUUCUUUACUCUUAAUUUUUUUUUGAGACAGAGUCACCCAGGCUGGAGUGCAGUGGUGAGAUUUUGGCUCACUAUAACCUCUUCCUCCAGGGUUCAAGUGAUUCUCCCACCUCAGCCUCCCAAGUAGCUGGGACUACGGGCACAUGCCACUGCACCUGGCUAAUUUUUAUAUUUUUGGUAGAGACAGGGUUUCACCAUGUUGGCCAGGCUGGUCUCAAACUCCUGACCUCAAGCGAUCCACCCACCUAGGCCUCCCAAAGUGCUGGGAUUACAGGCAUGAAUCACCACAACUAGCCUACCCUUAGAUUUUUGGAAGGAUCGAUCUUAUUUAACUAUGUGUGGAACAACCCAGUAAUAUCAGACUCGAAUUACUAUUUCAUUCUAUUUCAAAUGCUUAUAAAGCUACUAUUGUAGAUUAUAGUGUUAAUGCAAAGUUUACAGACUUUUGAUAUGGAAAACCAGAUAAAACAAUGUUACAAAAGGCAAAUAUAAAGAGUAUGUUUUCUUUUUAGUGCUUUGGAAAAAUUUCACUUAAACUCUUAUUACUGUAUAGAUUAAGCCCUAUAAUGCUAUUUAUAUUCCAGGGGAACGAAAAUCUGAAUUUGUUUUAUGAUUUAAAGCAUCUGGUUUGCAUAUUGUAUUGUAAUACUGAUACAGUUUGGCUGUGUCCCCACCAAAUUGAAUUGUGUUAAUAGUUCCCAUAAUCCCUACGUGUUGUGGGAGGGACCCAGUGGGCAGUAAUUUAAUCAUGGUGGUGGUUACCCUCAUGCUGUUCUUGUGAUGGUGAGUUCUCAUGAGAUCUGAUGGGUGUUUUUUUUUGUUUUGUUUUUUGUUUUUUGAGAUGGAGUUUUGCUCUUGUUGCCCAGACUGGAGUGCAAUGGCACACGAUCUCGGCUCACCGCAACCUCUGCCUCCUGGGUUCAAGCGAUUCUCCUGCCUCAGCAUCUCGAGUAGCUGGGAUUACAGGCAUGCACCACCACGCCCAGCUAAUUUUGUAUUUUUAGUAGAGACGGGGUUUCUCCAUGUUGGUUAGGCUGGCCUCAAACUCCCGACCUCAGGUGAUCCGCCCGCCUGGGCCUCCCAAAGUGCUGGGAUUACAGGCGUGAGCCACUGCUCCUGGCCCAAGAUCUGAUGGUUUUGUAAGGGAAUUUUCCCCCUUUGCUUGGCACUUCUUCCUGCUGCCAUGUGAAGAAGGAUGUGUUUGCUUCCCCUUCCACCAUGAUUGUAAGUUUCAUGAGGCCUCCCCAGCCUGUGGGACUGUGAGUCAAUUAAACGUGUUUACUUUAUAAAUUACCCAGUCUCAGGCAAUUCUUUAUAGCAGUGUGAGAACAGACUAAUAUGAAUACCAAUACUGAAAAAUUGUUUCUUGCCUCACCUUGUCCUAUGAACAGGAAUUAAAUUUUAAAGUAUUGCCUUAAGAUGGCUGUGCUAAAUAAUAAUCAUUGCAAGAGCAAUACUUUUACCUGUUUCUAGAUGACAAUAUUACUAAAAUUUCUCAAAUGAAGACUUUGUUUUAGCUUCAAUUACUUCAGAAAAUAUAAAUUUUAAAGAUGACUAUGAGAUAAAUCAUGAACUCAGUGGAAUUUUCAGAUGAGAUGGGGCGCGUUCAGGGUGGUAUGACUGUAGACGGAAUUUUCAGAUCUUUGUUAUUUAGAAGCAAGUAUAGGUAUAACGUGGACUAUCAACUGAUAUCUGCAAAUAAUUUGGUUAAAAUGAAAUUUGAUUGUAGUAUUUGUUGCUGUAGGAUUAUAAAUGUCAAAUAUCAUUGUAAACAUUUCUAUAUUUUUAGAAAUAUCUUGGGUGGCCUGAAACAGAAGUGAGGAAAUCAAUUUUUUAAGGUGAGCCAUUUGGCUUUUUUAAAAAAUUGAGAUUCAACUUACAUACCAUAAAGUUCACUCUUCUAAAGUGUACAAUUCAUUGGUGUUAGUAUAUUUACAGAGUUGUACAACUAUUACCACUAUAUAAUCCCAGAACACUUUCAUCACUCCAAAAAGAAACACCAUACCCACUACCAGUCACUCCUCAUGCCCCCUUCCUAUGACCCCUGGCAGCCAUUAAUCUACUUUCUGUCUCCUUGAAUUUGGAUUUUCUGGACACUUCAUAAAAAUUGAAUAAUACAAUAUAUGAACUUUUAUGUUUGACUUCUUUCACUUAGCAUAAUGUUUUCAGAGUGCAUCACUGUUGUAACAUGUAUCAGUACCCUUUUUGUGACUGAAUAUUAUUCCACCGAAUGGAUAUACCACAUUUUACUUAUCCAUUCAACCGUUGAUGUACAUUUGAGUUGAUUCCAAAUUUUGGCUAUUAAGAAUGCUGCUCUGAACAUUCAUGUGCAAGUUUUUUUUUUUUUGUAUGUACAUAUGUUUUCAAUUUUCUUGGAUAUAUAUCUAAGAAUUAGAAUUGCUGGAUCAUACAGUAAUUCUGCUUAACCUUUUGAGGAGCUGCCAGGCUGUUUUCCAAAGUGGCUACAACAUUUUGCAUUUCCACCAGCAUGUGUUUGAGGGUUCCAUUUUCUCCUCAUUCUUGACAACAUUUAUUACUCCCUUUUUAAAUUUUAGUCAUCAUAGUGUGGGUGAAGAAGUGUCUCACUGAGGUUUUGAUUUGCAUUUCCUUAAUGACUGAUGAUGUGGAGCCUCUUUCCAUGUGUUUAUUGACUUUUUAUAUAUUUUGGAGUAAUAUCUGUUCAUAUCCUUUGUCCAUUUUCAAUUUGUUUAUGUUCAUAUCCUUUGUCCAUUUUCAAUUUGUUUAUCUUUACUGUUGAGAUGUAAGAGUUUUUUUAUAUAUUUUCUGGAUACUAAACCAUUAUAUAUUGAUUUGCAAGUAUUUUAUUCCAUUCUGUGGCUUGUCUUUUCACUUUCUUCGUAGUGUAGUUUGAAGCACAAAAGUUUUUAAUUUUGAUAAAGUCCAGUUUGUUUUUUUCCCUUCAGUUCUUUGUGCUUGGUUUUAUAUCUUUUUUUUUUUUUUUUUUUUUUUUUGAGAUGGAGUCUUGCUUUGUCACCCAGGCUGGAGUGCAGUGGCGCGGUCUCAGCUCACUGCAACCUCUGCCUCCCAGAUUAAAGGGAUUCUCCUGCCUCAGCCUCCUGAGUACUGGGAUUACAGGCACCCACCACCAUGCCUGGCUAAAUUUUUGUAUUUUUAGUAAAGACAUGGUUUUGCCAUGUUGGCCAGGCUGGUCCUGAACUCCUAACCUCAAGUGAUCCACCAACCUUGGCCCCCAAAAGUGCUGAGAUUACAGGUGUGAGCCACCUUGCCUGGCCUUGGUUUUAUAUCUUAAAAGCUAUUCCUUCAUUCAAAGUCACGAAGGUUUACACUUAAUUUUUUUCUAUCUAAAAAACCAUUGCUUCAUCUAAAGUCAUGAAGAUUUACACUCUUUUUUUUUCUAACAGUUUUACAGUUUAGGCUCUUAUCAUUAGGUCUUUCAUUUAUUUUGAAUUAUUAUCAUUAUUAUUAUUUUCUUUUUGAGGCAGGGUCUCACUCUGUCACGCAGGCUUGUGUGCAUUGGUGCAAUCACAGCUCACUGCAGCUUCAGCCUUCUGGCCUCAAGCAGUCCUCCCACCUCAGCCUCCCAAGUAGCUGAGAUUACAAGUGUGUGCCACCAUGCCUGACUAAUUUUUAAAAUUUUUUUGUGAAGACAGUUUCUCACUCUGUUGCCCAAGCUGGUCAUCUCAAACUUCCAGACUCAAACAAUACUCCCACUUUGGCUGCCCAAAGUGCUGGGAUUACAGGCAUGAGUCACCAUUCCUGGCAUUAAUUUUUGUAUAUGGUGUGAGGUAGGGGUCCAGUUUCAUUUUUUUGCAUGUGGAUAUCCAGUUGUCCCAGCAUCAUUUGUUGAAAAGACUAUUUCUUCAUUGAUUUUUUUCUGCCACCCCUGUUUAAAAUCAGUUGCCCAUGAGUGUAUGGGUUUGUUCCUGGACUUGAAAUUAUGUUUCAUUGAUCUAUAUAUCUAUGCUAGUACCACAUGUCUUCAUUACUGUAGCUUUGUAGUAACUUUUGAAAUUGGGGAAGUGUGAGUUCCCCAACUUUAGUUCUCCUUCAGGAUUGUUUUGGCUAUUCUGGGUCUCUUGCAUUUUCAUGUGAGUUUAGAUUCUGCUUAUCGAUUUCUUUUUUUUCUUUUUUUUUUUUUUUGAGAUAGCAUCUUGCUUUGUCACCCAGGCUGGAGUGCUAUGGCUCAAUCUCAGCUCACUGCAACCUCCGCCUCCUGGGUUCGAGAGAUUCUCCUGCCUCAGCCUCCAGAGUAGUUAGGACUACAGGCGCGUGCCACCAUGCCAGGCUAAUUUUUGUAUUUUUAAUAGAGAUGAGGUUUCAUCAUGCUGACCAGGCUGGUCUCGAACUCCUGACAUCAAGUAACCCGGCUGCCUCAGCCUCCCAAAGUGCUGGGAUUACAGUCGUGAGCCACCAUACUCAGCCUAAGAUUCAGCUUACCAAUUUCUGCAAAAAAGCCCACUCAUUUUUAAUAGGAGGUAAAAAGCAGUUGACAUUUAUAACUUAGAGUCUUUUAAUGUUAGUGCUGAAAGGGACUAGAGAGCUCAUCUAAUUCAACCCACUUAUUUUAGUAUUGAAUGAAUGACCCUGUACAAGGAAAGGGAUUUGCUUGAGAUCCACACAGCUGUUUAAAGGCAGAGUUGGGAUUGGAACCAAGUCUUAGAGAAUCCAUUGUUGCUUCUACACUGCAUUAUUGCUUUGGUUCCCUAGUGUACAUUCACUUUGCUUAGGAGUGAUAUGUUCAGUUUAUCUUCUCUAAGAAUGGCAGCUGUUAUUUAGGACAGUGGCAUGCUGAGAAAUAGAUUGAUUUCUAUUCUAUACUGUGUCCAGUAAAGGUCGGGGGAGAAAGAGUAAAUCUUAUCUUCUUCUGUACUUUUCUUUGAUUAAUGUAAGAGUCUAGAGUUUUAUCAGAAGAUUAUUGUCCUUUAAAAUAUUGAUGGACUGAUUAUCACUUAAAGGGUAUAAACAGUGGGUAGUAAUUCAGUGAUUGAGAGGUUAAUUGCAGGUUUUUUUUUUUUUUUUUUCUGGUAACCAUAGAAUGAAUGUAGAAUGAAUUUGGAUUCAAUAAUGGGAACUAAGGUCAGGCGUGGUGGCUCACACCUGUAAUCCCAGCACUUUGGGAGGCCGAGGCGGGUGGAUCAUCUGAGGUCAGGAGUUCCAGACCAGCCUGGCCAACAUGGUGAAACCUCAUCUCUACUAAAAUUACGAAAAAUUAGUCAGGUGUGGUGACGGGUGCCUAUAAUCCCAGCUACUUGGGAGGCUGAGGCAGUAGAAUCGCUUGAACCCGGGAUGCGGAAGUUGCAGUGAGCCAAGAUCACGCCACUGUACUCCAUCUUGGGCGACAGAGCGCAACUCUGUCUCCAAAAAAAAAAAAAAAAAAGGGCAGGGGGAGCGGCUAGAGAAGGAACAUUCAAAUCUUCCCACGUGGGCAAGUUCCAAGCAAAUGUUUAUUUUUUUACCUCCUCUUUGGUUUUUGUCUCACUUGAAGCACUUUGUGUUUAUGGGAAAAUACCAAAAAUUACCAAAAUUUAAAAACCCAGGGCUUUGCUGGAAGUGAGGGUAUCUUCUUGGCUUUUCCCUUUUCCUCCCCACCACUAUACGCACAUGCACACACAGCUCUAUUUUUUGGUGCUUUUCGUUCAUUAUUCACUCCAUUUCAUUUUAGCUCUUGAAGUCAAAAUGGGAUUCCAAAGAGCAAAAUAGAAGUUUGGAGAGUUUGAAAUCUCUCCUCGUGGCUGGACGCCGUGGCUCACACCUGUGAUCCCAGCACUUUGGGAGGCCAAGGCAGGCAUACUGCUUGAACUCAGGAGUUCAAGACCAGCCUGGGGAACAUGGUAAAACCCUGUCUCUACAAAAAAUAGAAAAAUUAGCUGGGCAUGGUGGCUGUAGUCCCAGCUAUUUGGGAGGCUGAGGUGGGAGGAUCACUUGAGCCUGGGGAGGUUGAGACUGCACUGAGUCUUGAAUGAAUGAAUCCAUCUCUCUUUCUCUCUCCAUAUAGUCAAAGAGAACCAAAAAUGUAUGUGCUUUUUUUGUGAAAUUGUUAAGGAUUCCAUGAUCCUACUAAAAUUUUUGAUAAUGAUAAUUUCAAGUGGAGAAUAUAUAAAGGACUCGUGAGGCCUUCCUACCUCAUUUUCUGAGGUUAUGUUGACUUUAAUAUCCAAUGUAUCAUAGGUGUUUUCUUUUUUCUCUGACAAUUGUUAUGUUAAAAACAAAAAGAAGCACAUACUGUACAGUCAAAACUAUCAGACGUAACUCUGUGGGAAACUUUAUUCCAAGGGUGCUGCCACUGCCCUUGUUUUAAAUAUUUUUGGAACUUCAUUUCUCUUCAGGUCUAUUUAAUAAGCUUGUUAGGAAUAUUGUAAAUUAUUUUAGAAACACAUUGUGGUCUCAGCCUCAUGUGGCAUUGCCACUUGUUACUACAUGACCCCCCCACACCCCCUAAAAAAGAAAAAGGACUUUAAAAACCCUCUCAGGACAAACAUUUGCUACCGUGGUUGAUUUUUUAAUUUUACAUUAACUAUUUAAUAUCAGACUAUAACUAAAAUACAAGUAGUGGAAUUAUACUUUUAUAAAGUAUCAAAUUAUGUAGAUGAUGACGAAGUUAUAAGGUUACUAUAAUUUCCAACUUCACCCAUAGGUCAUGGUAUAGUUGAAAUUUCAUAUUUAAAUAUCAAAACAUAAAUGUCUAAAGAGAUUGUGUAAAUUCUUUAUCAGUUAUAAGGAAAAACCAAAUUCAAAUUCUUAAGGUUUUUCUUAUAUGUGAUUUUUUUUUUUUUUUUUUUUUUGAGACAAACUUGCAGGGAGAGAAUUAUGUGGCAUGAGGAGGAUUGAGAAUGUUGUUCAUUUUAUCUAAUUACUGCCUAUUAAGAAAAGCUUCACAUUUAUUUCAGCUAUUCUAUUGAAUACUUUUACCUAAGAUAAUGAAACCGUUAAGUAGAGAUUUUUCUAAUAGUAUAAAAAUCAGUGUAGGCCCAGCACAGUGGUUCACACCUGUAAUCCCAGCACCUUGGGAGGCUAAAGGCAGGAGGAUUGCUUGAGCUCAGGAGUUUGAGACCAACCUGGGCAACAUAGUGAGAACUCAUCUCUAUUAAAAAUCAGAAAAAUUGGCCAGGUGUGGUGGCUCAUGCCUGUAGUCCCAGUUACUCAGGAGGCUGAGGCAGGAGGAUCCCUUGAGAUUGAGGCUUCAGUGAGCUAAUGAUCGCGCCACUGCACUCCAGCCUGGGUGACAGAGUGAGACCCUGUCUCAAAAACAACAAAAAUCUCAGUGUGACAAAUUCCUAACAGCUCAAAUACUACUUGUCUUAUUUGUUAACUAUUUUGAAAUAAUUUUAAACUUACAGAAAAGUAGAAUAGUUCAAAAGAUCCUGUAUAUCCUUCCCCUAGAUUCUUCUAUUGUUAACAUCUUGCCAUAUUUUCCAUACCACUCUCUAGCUAUGUAUUCACAUUAUUUUUUGAACUGUUUGUUACUAAGUUGCAAUUGUGAUGUCCCAUUAGUACUAAAUACUUAAGUGUAUACUUUUUAAAAACAAGGACACUCCUACAUAACCACAGUACUUAAAAUCAGGAAACCAGCAUUGAUAAAAUUCUACCAUUUGAUCCACGAACCCCAUUCAAAUGUUGCCAUUUACUCCAAAAAUAUCCUUACAAUAACCCUUUCCUUUUUUGGUCCACAGUCCAAUCAGGAUGAAGCACGCAUUUAGUUACAUUUUCCCUUUAGUCUUCCUCAAUCUGGAGCGGUUCCUUGGUUUUUCCUUUUUUGUGACCUUGACAUUUUUGAAGAAUGCAGGCCAGGUACUUUGUAGAAUGAUGUGCACUUUGGGUUUGUCUGAUAUUUCCUCAAGAUUAGAUUCAGGUUGUGAAUUUUUGGCAGGAAUACCAGAGAGGUGAUGCUGUCUUCUUCUCUGCAUUGUAUCAGGAGGCACAUCAUGUCAAUUUUUUCCAUUACUGGUGAUGUUAAUUUUUAACAGUUGGUUACGAUGUUUUCAAGAUUUCUCCACUGUUAGUAUUUUCUCCACUUGUAUUUGUUUUUUGGUAUAAACUUAAAAAGUACAGCAUGAUGUUUUGGUAUAUGUAUCCAUAGUGAAAUGAUUAUUACAGGUAUUAAUUAAUGAGGAAUUACGUAUUUUGUGGGUAGCUAUUUUGAGACUCUCAAUAUCCUAUUUCUCAAAAUUUUACCCUUUACUUUUAGCAUCCAUUGAUGAUCCUUGUCUGGAUCAGUUAUUGCCAAAUGGUAGUUUUCUUUUCUUUUCUUUUCUUUUGAGACAGUGUCUUGCUCUGUUGCCCAGGCUACAGUGCAGUGAUGAGAUCAUAGCCCACUGCAGCCUCAAACUCCUGGGCUCAUGCCAUUUUCCCCUCAGCUUUUGGAGUUAGCUGGGACUACAGGCAUGCAUCACCACACCCAGAUUAUUUUUAAAGUUUUUGUAGAAACGGGGUCUCUUCUUCCCCAUUUAUUCAAUAUUUAUAUCAGUAUAGAACAUGGGUCCCUGUUUUAUCAUCUGUAAGUUAUGAUUUAUUUUGAUGCCCCCAUUGUCCAAGAUUUGACUAGCGAGAGCACUUUCCAGCUAGCUCCUGUGUCCUUUGGACAUACCCCAUGGUUCAUUGAGCACUUCCUUGCUUUCUGGCACCACAAGAUGUUCCAGGCUCGUCUUCUAUUUUCCCUACCCCGCUCCUGACAUCAGCCAUUUCUCCAAAGAGUCCUGGUUCAUAUUAGUGGAGAAUGGUAUUUAAAACCAAGAUCCGGAUGCUAAAGGCUGUGCUCAUUGCCCCUGUGCUAGCAUUGCCACUGUGCGUUCUCCCAGUGGACAAAUUUGGAAAUAUAUGCGUCUAUGCUUGUUACCUCAUCCAUCCAUAUAUAUAUUAAAAACAAGUACACACUGAUACCUAUUUCACAUCUACUCCACAGAGUUUAUUCUAGUCUUCUCCCUUUCCACAAUUGUAUCUUCUCCACCCUAUAUUUAAAAACUGGACUUCCAGAGUCUCCAAUACAUUGGCUUAUUUGUUCAUUUUCCCUGUGAUUAACCAACCUCCUGACCACGUGGCUGGCUCCUUUGCUCCAUCUCUGCCCCUCACCCCCUACCGUACAUCACUGCUGUGAGGACCAAGUUUCCUCCCUUUCCUCGAUCCAUGACAGCACCUGCCAGUUGAACCCCACAGUGGGAAUUUUAAAGAAGGCACUUUUGGCUCAGAUGGCAGUGCCAAAGCAGGCAUUCCAAUUCACAUGGUGCUCUAGCAAUUGUGAAAUAAACAGAUUCUGAAGGUC